GCUCCGACCGGCCCCGGAGCCGCCGCCGCCGCCGCCCGCCCGCCCGCCCCGCGCCGGAGCCGCCCGCCCGCCCCCCGCGCCCCGCGCCCCGCGCUGCAGCCGACGCCCGCCCGGGCCGCGCGCAAACUUCCCGGGCCGGCGGGCAGGGGCGGCGGCGGCGGGGCCCGGAUGGGAGCCCGGGCCGGCGGCGGCGGCGCCCAUGGACACUAACCGCCCGGGCGCGUUCGUGCUGAGCAGUGCCCCGCUGGCCGCGCUGCACAACAUGGCCGAGAUGAAGACGUCGCUGUUCCCCUACGCGCUGCAGGGUCCGGCCGGCUUCAAGGCGCCCGCGCUGGGGGGCCUGGGCGCGCAGCUCCCGCUCGGGACCCCGCACGGCAUCAGCGACAUCCUGGGCCGGCCCGUGGGCGCGGCGGGCGGGGGCCUCCUGGGGGGGCUGCCCCGGCUCAACGGGCUCGCGUCGUCCGCCGGCGUUUACUUCGGGCCCGCGGCCGCUGUGGCGCGCGGCUACCCCAAGCCCCUGGCCGAGCUGCCGGGGCGCCCGCCCAUCUUCUGGCCCGGCGUGGUGCAGGGCGCGCCCUGGAGGGACCCGCGUCUGGCUGGCCCGGCCCCGGCCGGCGGCGUCCUGGACAAGGACGGGAAGAAGAAGCACUCGCGCCCGACCUUCUCGGGCCAGCAGAUCUUCGCGCUGGAGAAAACCUUCGAGCAGACCAAGUACCUGGCGGGCCCGGAGCGCGCGCGUCUCGCCUACUCGCUGGGCAUGACCGAGAGCCAGGUGAAGGUCUGGUUCCAGAACCGCCGGACCAAGUGGCGCAAGCGGCACGCGGUGGAGAUGGCGUCGGCCAAGAAGAAGCAGGACUCGGACGCCGAGAAGCUGAAGGUGGGCGGCUCGGACGCGGAGGACGACGACGAAUACAACCGGCCCCUGGACCCCAACUCGGACGACGAGAAGAUCACGCGGCUGCUCAAGAAGCACAAACCCUCGAACUUGGCGCUGGUCAGCCCGUGCGGCGGCGGCGCGGGGGACGCCUUGUGAGGACCCGCGGGGUGGGGGCGAAUCUAUUUUUGCAGAAUCCGGGGGCGGCCCCGGGUGGGCGCGAGUCGCUUUGUAUCAUCAAUAAAUUAUUUAACGGGUCCCCGUCGGAGCCGUCGCUCCGGAGCCUGCGCCGCGUGUUUCUUCCGUCUCGAACCCGGAGCGAGGCGGCCCCUCCCCGGCCCCGGCUUCGCCCCUGCGCCCGCCUCGGGUCCUCCGGGUUCCCGGUGCGGAGGCUGCGGGCCCCGGGCAGGCGCGAGGAGGCGGCGAAGGCGCAGGGAAGGGGCCCGGCCCGCGGGAAGGAACCGCAGCGACAGCCGCCAGGAGCCCGGGACGGAGCCGGGGACGGAGCAGCAGGUACGGCCCGGCCCGCCUCGCCUCGGGGCGGAUUCGGACGCGCUUGGGGGUUCCCGAAAGGGCGGGUGAGCCGCGUACCCGCCUCGAGUCCCCGCGGGAGGUUUUUCUUCUUCCGUUUUCCCGCUUUGGGGCCACGUACUCGUUGCCACCGGGCACCCGUUCCCGCUUGGCCGAGGGCUUCGCUCUGAUUAUUUCCAAAGUCCCUCUGCGCAUCAGCGGAUCCCAUAGGCCCGCCCUGGGCUCAGCCGGUGGAACCGGGUCUGAUCCGCUGCACGGAGGCCCUUCGGUCACCAUCCCGCCAGAUCUUCCCGCGGUGGAAAGCAGUUUCUUCCGAACUAGGACCGCAAAGAGAAAUCCGAAAUAAUUCCGCCCGCGGAGCGGCGGGGCCUCCCGUGGGUCACGCGGGGUCAGGGAGCCGGAGGCCCCCUGGGCAAGGCCCGCAGCGCCCAGCCGGGGGCUCGGGGGACCCGUCUCCUGCCCUGAAAUGCCGCCAGCUCCGCGGGGCUGUGACUGCGGCUGACAAAACCCCUCCAGCCUCCCGCAGCCUCUGUGGCCGGGGCUGCCCAUCGCUGCAUCUUAAUGGGCGUGGCUGUUGAGUUUUAAUUUUUAAAAAUUAAAUGUAAAUAAUGAUAUCACUGCGGUGGUACGAUUUCUCUUGGCAUUUGCGGAAGCGUUAAAGGGAAAUAGAAAGGGCUUAAACUCGGCGCGUUUUGUUUUAGGCUCUUAGCAGCCUUCUUUACAAGGAAGCAACUCGAAGGGCAGAAGCAACGCUUUUCUGUGGGGAGCCCCUCUCAGCUCAGAGCAGAGGGGCUUCUUAAAGUUUUGAGGAAGGCAAAGCGUUGAUAUAAUCCCGUUUUAAAAUGUUGAGGGAUAAAUCCUUUAUUACAGUAGAAAGUCCAAAAGGCUGUGUUUCUCCUCUCAAUGAACGGCUUAGUGUUUUGUGACAGCGUGUGAUACAGUGAAAUUCCAGGAUUUCUAAUGAGCUUGAUCUCAAAUAACAGGCUAUACAGGAGGCCGCUCCCCUGAGUUAGCAUUUCAAAGGUGGCAGGAGAAGGGAAAGGAAGAAAAAGCAACACGGGACUAUUUUCACCACGGUCAAUUUUAUUGCUUAGGAACCAGACCGGUCACUUCCAAAGGCCCCUCAGAACGACCAACAGCUGAAACCCGCGGGGCGGACUCCGUGUUGAACCGCGGACAGCGGCAACCACAGCAGCGACACGGACCUGUGCUUCCACCAAGAACAGAUUCCGCAGCGGACAGCAGUCACUUGCAGUGGUAGUAUUUAUCCCACACAAACACCCAGCUAAUGCCUUCACCCGGUCCAGGAACUCUGUAGUGUUCUAAAGUAAAAUCAAUAAAACAUACAUUUGUGUUUCAUCAA